AGAAGCGCUAGGGAUAUCUCCCCUCCCCCGCUCCCUCUGUCUCCCUCUCUCCCUCCCCUCUCCCCUCUCCCAUGAGAGGACACAGCCAGAAGGAGACCGUCUGCAAGCCAAGGAGAGAAGCCUCACCAGCCAUGGAAUCUAUAGGCACCUUGAUGUUGGACUUCCAGCCUCCAGAGCUAUGGAAGCCAACCGUCGGGAGCACACACACCACAUUACAAGGAUCCCAGCCAGGCCCAGGAGGGGAAGCAAGGACACCCUAGAGGCAGAGAGAACUGGCAGGCUGGAGUGAAGUGGCAUGAUCUCAGCUCACUGGAAUGUCCACCUCCUAGGUUCAAGUGAUUCUCCUGCCUCAGCCUCCCAAGUGGCUGGGAUUACAGGAUUUUUCAUGGGCCGAUCUGCUGAAUUCAGCCUAGGAGCUGAGACCAACAUCUGAGUCUCUUCAGCACACAAGUUUGAAAGAAGUCCUAGCAACUUCAAGCUCAGAACUACGGGUGGCAGCAGCUCCCUCUUGACGUCGAAGCCUCCCAUUCCAGAGAGAGUCAAGGCCUGGAUCAAACAAAGCCCACAAGCACCGAUGACUGAGCUGCUGACUACCCCCAGCAUCUCCAACUCAACCUCCUCUUUCUGCCUCUACCCAAAUUUUAAAACUUUCAAACAUGGGUUUAAAAAUGGUAAUGAGUAAAGUUGCAUCCAAGUGUAUCAAAUAAAACUAAAUAUCCAUAAAUGCUGUAAUAAUUCCUGCUUUGAUGCUGAACUAAAGAAUUUUCUGCCAGGCGUGGUGGCUAACACCUGUAAUCCCAGCACUUUGGGAGGCCAAGGCAGGUGGAUCACGAGGUCAGGAGUUCAAGACCUGCCUGGCCAACGUGGUGAAACCCCAUCUCUACUAAAAAUACAAAAAUUAGCUGGGCAUGGUGGCAGGCAUCUGUAGUCCCAGCUACUCAGGAGGCUGAGGCAGGAGAAUCACUUGAACCCGGGAGACAGAGGUUGUAGUGAGCCAAGAUGGCACCACUGCACUCCAUCCUGGGCAACAAGCGAGAUUCCAUCUCAAAAGAAAAAAAAAAAAGAAUUUUCUGUUUAUAUUACAUAUAGUCUCACUUCAUAUUUCAUUUCUCUCACCUCUGAUACCUGGAGUCCUUUGCUAGUACUGAAAUUGAGUAAAGUCAUUCUCAUGAGUUUUAGUAAACUCAAAACUCAAAACUCAUGAAGUUGGCAAAACUCAAAGAAUGCUUUGGUCUAGUUUGACAUUGGCCAGUAUGUUUUUCAUAUCCAGUCAUUCCUUUUUUCCUGGCUGACAUCCUCACUUCCUGCCUGUGGAGGAAAAGUUAAAUAUUAAAUUUGAACUCAAUUGAAUGUGGACACAAACAAUGGUCACCAAGUCCGGGAACAGGUUGUGUGAGUCCCUUGAGGCAUUUAUCCUGCCCUGUUUCGGAGAAAUCUCUAUUUCAAACUAUUCCUAUGUGUUACUUACUGAAAAACAACAGACAAUCGCAAAAACAAGUUGACCUUUUUGUGUUCCUUGAGCCCAGUCACAAAGGGCCCUCAUGACUGGGCCUCAUGCCAAACAACUUGUUACAAAAAGAGCUAGGGUCCCAGACCGCACCAAAGACCCAUGAGACCUCUCCUCGUCUGUGCACAGACUGGUGGCCGACUCUGGAGCCCAGGCUGUUGCUUCCUGGUCUGGUGAUGAAUCCUCCAUAGUCUGGGGUCUCACUUUGUUGCCCAGGCUGGCCUAUUCCAGGAUUUGACUUUGCAGUUGAUUCCCUAGACAUGUGAAGAUCUGAGUCUAAUCAAAGAUAAUUCAGAGAUCGUCAGGGUAACAUGCAAGGACUGGAAAGGGGUCUCCAGUCACCUCUCAUGAGGAGACGCGUCCCACUGCCUCAUUGAGGUGGCCUCAGGGUGAAGAAUCAGGACCCACCUGGUGCAACGAAUAAACCCAGACUCUCAGCAUCGCGAGGAGAAAAAGUCUUGCAACACCGUGGCGACCAAGUAACUCUGUGCACAUACUAAGGUCUCAAAACACAGGCACGGCCCCUGGAGUUCCCAGUACAUCAACAUCAGCCUGGGGAUCAUGUCCUCAUCAAAAGCUGGAAAGAGGAGAAACUCGAACCAGCCUGGGAAGGACCUUACCUGGUGCUCCUAACACUGAAACCACAGUCCAGAUAGCAGAAAAAGGAUGGACCCAUCACACCCCAGUCAAGAAAGCAUCACCACCUCCGGAGUCAUGGGCCGUUAUCCCAGGGGAAAACCCUACCAAACUAACGCUAAGAAAAGUUUAACUCUCCUUCAUCUAUUCUAUUACUCCUUCUUCUUUCCUCAUUCUAUGGCUGACCACCUCAUUAUUAAUGUAACCAGGUCAAGCUCACCCCAAACUAUUACCUUCGAUGCAUGUCUUGUCAUACCCUGUGGAGAUCUCCAAAGUCAAAAGCAACUCUCAGACUCAGAGAAGUAUCUCUGCCCCUUUAAGAUAAAAGGCUCCCCCUAUCAAGACCCUUGUUCCUUAACGAAUGCAGGAAAACAGGUCUGCCAUAGCUGGAAUGAUGUUGUGUGGACAACUGAAUAUCAAGGCUGGACCUCGUCAACCGGUGGUUGUAUGUCCUUAAAACCAUACAUUCACUUCACUAAAGAAAGUACCCCCCAUAAUUGCCAGUAUAACCAAUGUAAUCCAGUGCAAAUUUCUAUUCUCAUUCCAACUUCUACUGACCCUAAACCUACUUUAAGUUGCUUAUAUGGCAUGGGAGCCGAAAUAGCAGGGGCACAUCUUAUUGGAUAUUUUGAGAUAUGUUUUAUUACUCCUUCACCUCCUACAUUCCUUCUACAUUAUCCCCCAAUGUUCUGUUCUUCCUCCACCCAAAGAUAAAACCAAAAUAGAUAUUGUAGAAGUAAAUGACCUAAAACAAACUUUAGCAAUUGAAACAGGAUAUCAAGAUGCAAAUGCCUGGAUGGAAUGGAUUAAAUAUUCCGUCCACACUUUAAACAAAAGCAAUUGUUAUGCUUGUGCGCACAGCAGGCCAGAGGCCCAGAUUGUCCCCUUUCCACUCAGAUGGUCCUCCCGUCGACCAAGCAUGGGCUGUAUGGUAGCUCUCUUCCAGGAUUCUACAGCUUGGGGCAAUAUAUCAUGCCAAGCUCUCUCUCUGCUCUAUCCUGAAGUUCAACACCCUGCGGGUCAGCCCCCGAGGGCCAUCCAGCUUCCGUCUCCCAAUGUCAGUUUCAUCUCAUGUCUCUCAUGACAAGGGAAAACUUGGCAUUCCGUGGAAGCUUAAUGGGAUGUAGUGAGCUUAAGCCCUUCCAAGAGCUUACCCAUCAGUCUGCUGUUAGUCAUUCUCGAGCGGAUGUAGCGGAUGUAUGGUGGUAUUGUGGUGGACCCUUACUGGACACUCUGCCAAGUAACUGGAGUGGUACUUGCACUCUUGUCCAAUUCGCUAUCCCUUUUGCCCUUGCAUUUCUUCAACCAGAAAAAGAAAAGCCACAACACCGUAAAAUAAGAGAAGCCCCUUAUGGGUCUUUUGACUCUCAAGUUUAUUUAGACGCAACUGGAGUCCCACAGGGAGUACCACACAAAUUCAAAGCUCAAGACCAGAUAGCUGCAGGAUUUGAAUCAAUAUUUUGGUGGGUAACUAUCAGUAAAAACAUAGAUUGGAUAAAUUACAUCUAUUAUAACCAGCAGCGGUUUAUUAACUACACUAGAGAUGCUGUCAAAAGAAUAGCUGAACAGUUAGGGCCUACUAGCCAGAUGGCUUGGGAAAACAGAAUGGCCCUAGACAUGAUAUUAGCCAAAAAAGGUGGAGUUUGUGUUAUGAUCAAAACUCAAUGUUGUACCUUCAUCCCAAACAAUACUGCCCCUAGUGGGAGCAUAACAAGGGCCUUACAAGGCCUUACUGCUUUAUCCAAUGAAUUAGCUAAAAAUUCUGGAGUCAAUGACCCUUUUUCAGGAUGGCUAGAAAGGUGGUUUGGUAAAUGGAAAGGAAUCAUAGCCUCAAUUCUUACUUCUCUUGCAGCCGUAAUAGGUGUAGUCAUUCUUUUUGGGUGUUGUGUCACACCAUGUAUCCGUGGGCUAGUACAGAGGCUUAUAGAAACAGUACUUACUAAAACCUCCCUUAGCUCUCCUCCACCUUAUUCAGAUAAGCUUUUCCUUUUAGAGGAUCAAGUCGAACAGCAAAGCCAAGACUUGUUAAAAAGGUUUGAAGAGGAAGGACCAUAACAAUUGAAAGGGGGAAAUUAUAAGAUACAGUAAAUUCCUCUUCAAAGAUUUAGCCUGUUGACUUCCUUAUUCUUUGUUCUCAAACUCGACUUCCUUGUUGUCCAUGCCUCCUUGUCCCUAGUUACUGUGAACAACCUUCCCACCAGUUCUAAUCAAUAACUCACAUCUGCUCCCUUGGUUACCCACUCUGCACCCAUUCUUCCCACUGAAACUGCACUUCCCACCACUGUAACUCACAUCCCCCUUCCCUUCCUUAUUUGGAAAAGUAUUCACAAAUAGCCAAUCGGGUCAACUUAGAAUGAGCGGUCCAACCCCAGCCCCUGGGGGAGUGACACAGAGGUAGGGACUGUGUUAGGGAUAAAAACCUUUUCCUUCCUUUGUUCAGUGUGCUCCUGUGAUCAUGAUUGAUGCAGGCAGCACCCUUCUGCAGAAGUAAAUUGCCUUGCUGAGAAAA